UUUUUUUUUUUUUUUGAAAUGGAGUCUUGCCUCAUCGCCCAGGCUGGAGUGAAGUGGUAUGAUCUCAGCUCACUGCAACCUCUGCUUGCUGGGUUCAAGCAAUUCUCCUGCUUCAGCCUCCACAGUAGCUGGGAUUACAGGCACACACCACAAUGUCCGGCUAAUUUUUGUAUUUUUAGUAGAGACAGGGUUUCACCAUGUUGGCCAGGAUGGUCUCGAUCUCUUGACCUCGUGAUCUGCCUGCUUCGGCCUCCCAAAGUGCUGGGAUUACAGGCGUGAGCCACCGCACCUGGCUGGUAGUGGCCCUUUUUCAGGGGUUUACAGGUAAACUUUCCUUCCACUUUUUGAGAUCUGGGGACAUUACAUGGGAGUUGGAGGCAAGUCUCGGAAGGCUGCUGGGCCUUGUCCUGGGCGCAGGCUUCUUAGGCCCACCUCAGGGUUGCCAAGGGGCAGGUGUGCAGAUCCAUAGGGACCAGCACCGGGGCUCUUCCAAGCAGGGCAAAGGUGUUAAGGGAACAGAGGAGAGCAGGGGGAUUGGGGGCAUCAUGAGGAUGGAGGGGGACAAGGCCAGAUGGGGCUAAACCCAGUGGCCGGGUUUCCUUCUGAGUGCCCAGGAUGUUCCUAGGGAGCCCUCAGUGAGGGGUGCCCUAUUGUGGGUAUGAAGGAGGAGCAGAGAGCAGGGUCGGGGCCAGAGAAGGGGCUAGUGCUGGCAGCAUGGAGGCAGAGCCAGUGGAAUUGGCCUGUGAUUGGACAAGGAAUGGGCUCAGAAAGCAUCCUGGAUAGCUGGGCAUGGAGGUGCACUCACCUGUAGUCCCAGCCACUGGAGAAACUGGCGGGAGGAUCGCUUGAGCCCAGGACUUCCAACCUGUAGUGUGCAUGAUCACACUUGUGAAUAGACAGCGUACUCCAGCUAGGGAAACAUAGUGAGACCCCUGUUUCUAAAGAAAAAUGAAAGCCUCCUGGGUUUGGCUGAGUCCCUGGUGAAUGGUGGAGCGGUCCUGAGAGCUGGGAAGACCUCUUUCUGGCACAGCAACCGGGGCAGAGGUGAGAGGAGAAGGGCCUCAGCAGUGUUCUGGCCUUUUGGGUUCAUCCAAAACUUGCCGGUCCUGGGCCUGCUGGGAGAGGUCAGCCCCUUUCAGGUGAGCAGCUCUGGGGCCGGGUGACCCACGCCACCGUGUCGGGCACACAGUGGUGCUUCGUUUUCCUCACUCCUGGGGCCACAGCCUUCCUGCUGCGGUUCUGCCUGGUGGGUGGGUCCAUGCUGCUUUGAGGAGGCAAGUGACCUAAGGCUUCCGGGACACUCUUUUGGCAACUUGGGCCUUGGAAGGACAGCAGAGCAGGUGUGCAGUGUUAGGACCUGUGGCUGAGCUGACCUAACAGCCUGCCUGGAGGCAUCAGUCAGGCUCAAGUAGAACAGCAAGGCCCCCAUCUUGGGGCUGUCGUCCAGGCACAGAGCGGUCAGCAUCUACUGUCCUUCCUGGAGAAAAAAGGGAAAAUGCAUUUGUCAUUUAAAUGUUGGAAUGGGCCAGGCACGGUGGCUCCUACCUGGAAUCCCAGCACAUUGGGAGGGCAAGGUUGGAUCACAUGAGGCCAGGAGUUUAAGACCAUCCUGGCCAACAUGGUGAAACCCCAUCUGAAAAAUACAAAAAAUUAGCCACCUGUGGUGGCGGGUACCUGUGGUCCCAGUUACUUGGGAGGCUGAAGCAUGAGAAUUGCUUGAACCCAGGAGGUGGAGGUUGCAGUGACAGAUUGCUCCACUGCACUCCAGCCUAGGUGACAGAGCGUAAGACUCUGUUUAAGGAAAAAAAAAAAAAAAAAAAAGGAAUGGUUCUGAGAAGUCAUUCCUUAAGUAAAUAAAUUGCCACCCCAGGUUGCCCUCUUGGGAGGGGACUCUGGAGGCCGCCCUCCACCCUUAGGCCAGGGCCUGUCAGUCCCUGCCUCCCUGGGCUGCCUCCUGGGGAUCUCAGCCGACACCAUGCCCCUGUCCUUCCUCCACCUCUUUCCCAGGUUGCUCUGCCUGCAGUCCACCUUCUAGGAGUGAGCCCCCCCACCCCCACUGGAAGUCCCUCUCUAGCUGUCCCCAGUUCCCUGAAUCAAGACUGCUUCCCUGCCAGAGAGAUGACCCCAAUUCCUGCCUCCUCUCACUAGGCUCUCAGGGGCCGGGACUGGGGACAGAGCAUACUUAGAGCUAGCCCUGGCCCUCGGGCUGCUUUUGGAAGGAGGAGCAUGGCAGGCGAGCAUCAGGUGACACGUGCCCCCACGGGGAGCGCAAGAAGGCACUGGAGGCUGUUGCGAAGGAGCAGUGGGUUUCGGGUCCUCAUGACCGGCCCUGGUUCCGGGUGUGAGGCUGUGGAGACGCAUGGGUCUGCCUUUCUCAUCCGCAGCUUCCUGUUGCUACUUGGGAAGCUCCAUGUUUGCUGUCCGGUUGUGUUUCGAGUCUGUUCUCUUGGGCGUCUGUGCCGUGGAAGUUCCUUGUGCUUGAUAGGGCCAGCACGUGUGAACAAUCUUCACUUCAGCUAGAAGCUUUGAAGUCUUUGGACUCAAGCUUUACCCAAACCGCUUAUAAGGUUGGGGGGAACCGAGUGCCUGUCUCUCCCCGCUUUUUUUUUUGAGUGGAGUCUCGCUCUGUCACCCAGGCUGGAGCACAGUGGCGCGAUCUUGGCUCACUGCAACCUCAGCCUCCUGAGUAGCUGGGACUACAGGCGCCCGCCGCCACGCCCGGCUAAUUUUUUGUAUUUUUAAUAGAGACGGGGUUUCACCGUGUUAGCCAGGAUGGUCCCGAACUCCUGAUCUCAUGAUCUGCCCACCUCGGCCUCCCAAAGUGCUGAGAUUACAGGCGUGAGAGUUGUAGUUCGUUGAGAGGGAGACAGACCUCGAGGAAAUGCUUGGUGUGCCUGCCGGGUGACUGCUCGCUCUCCUUGUCUGCUCACUCUGCCCAGUGAAUGGGUCUAGGCAUCCUCAUUGUUCCCUUCCUCUGUCCUCAACAUCAGCCCAACCCUGACCAGGCCCCUUCCUGAGGUUCCCACACAACAGGGGCUCCAUGUUCAGAAGGGGAGAGAGAAACCCACCUGGGGAUGCUCUGUAAGGAGAGCAGAGCCCAGUGGAGUCUCUGCCCGGGACGCUGAGGGAGGAAGAGCUGCGGUUAAUUCAAAAGGAAGGGUGAGGUGCAGGUAUUGGCUGGAUGAUGCUCAGAGAAGCAGGAAGAGUGGGCAUGGCACUGAGUGGCUGAGGCCAUCACUGGUGGCCUUGGUGCUUAGGCAGAAGGAGAGGGCAUGGUGCAGGGCGCUGAGGCCGUCUGUGGCUGCCUUGGUGGGGCUUACUGAGUUCUAGUGGACAGCAAGGUGCCAGGGCAGGGCUGGCACAUGGAGGGCUCUGAAGGCCAUGUGUAUCGUCUGAAGUGAGGGAAACCCGUGGUAGCUAAAGGGAAUGCACUAGCCAGCCCCAGGUGCGCCACAUUCCUGCUCUAGGGGCUGGAGGGAAACCCGUGGUAGCUAAAGGGAAUGCACUAGCCAGCCCCAGGUGUGCUACGUUCCGCUCUCGGGGCUGGAGGGGAACCCGUGGUAGCUAAAGGGAGUGCACUAGGCAGCCCCAGGUGUGCUACGUUCCCGCUCUCGGGGCUGGAGGGAAACCCGUGGUAGCUAAAGGGAAUGCACUAGGCAGCCCCAGGUGUGCUACGUUCCCGCUCUCAGGGCUGGAGGGGAACCCGUGGUAGCUAAAGGGAGUGCACUAGCCAGCUCCAGGUGUGCUACGUUCCGCUCUCGGGGCUGGAGGGGAACCCGUGGUAGCUAUAGGGAGUGCACUAGCCAGCCUCAGGUGUGCUACGUUCCCGCUCUCGGGGCUGGAGGGGAACCCGUGGUAGCUAAAGGGAGUGCACUAGCCAGCCUCAGGUGUGCUACGUUCCCGCUCUCGGGGCUGGAGGGGAAUCCGUGGUAGCUAUAGGGAGUGCACUAGCCAGCCUCAGAUGUGCUACGUUCCCGCUCUCAGGGCUGGAGGGGAACCCGUGGUAGCUAAAGGGAGUGCACUAGCCAGCUCCAGGUGUGCUACAUUCCCGCUCUCGGGGCUGGAGGGGAACCCGUGGUAGCUAAAGGGAGUGCACUAGCCAGCCCCAGGUGUGCUACAUUCCCGCUCUAGGGGCUGGUCUGGCGGCAUGGCUCUCUCCUGAGUGCCUUCAGAGCCUGAGUGCCAGCAGGCAGGCGUCUCCUGCCCAGUGGGUUUGGUAAGAUAUAUUUCAGAAGGCAUCCACCACUCUAAAACAUGCUUAUUGCAGGAACCAUGGGGGAGACCAAAGGGCCUAGAGCCUUGAGAACCUCUGACCAUUAGUGUUAACAGGAAGGCAGCCUGUUCCCCUAGCUGGGGAGGGGGUUGUGCGUGGCAGGAAGCCCGUGCGUCUGUGUCUCUUUGGAGCUGUGGGUUGGUUGUGUGGAUGCCAGCUGUGUGGUCCCCAGCCUCACUGAGCCUGAGUUUCCAUACUAGCGGCGGGAGAUGGGACUAGAGGGUCUCCAAGGCUCCCUGAAGCUCUGCGAUUCUGCUUCUCUGAGUCUUGACCGCAGGGCUUUGUUCGCGGGGGUCACAGCUCUCAUGGCUGCAGCUAGCGUGACCCCCCCUGGCUCCCUGGAGUUGCUACAGCCCGGCUUCUCCAAGACCCUCCUGGGGACCAAGCUGGAAGCCAAGUACCUGUGCUCCGCCUGCAGAAACGUCCUCCGCAGGCCCUUCCAGGCGCAGUGUGGCCACCGGUACUGCUCCUUCUGCCUGGCCAGCAUCCUCAGCUCUGGGCCUCAGAACUGUGCUGCCUGUGUUCACGAGGGCAUAUAUGAAGAAGGCAUUUCUAUUUUAGAAAGCAGUUCGGCCUUCCCAGAUAAUGCUGCCCGCAGGGAGGUGGAGAGCCUGCCGGCCGUCUGUCCCAGUGAUGGAUGCACCUGGAAGGGGACCCUGAAAGAAUACGAGAGCUGCCACGAAGGCCGCUGCCCGCUCAUGCUGACCGAAUGUCCCGCGUGCAAAGGCCUGGUCCGCCUUGGUGAAAAGGAGCGCCACCUGGAGCACGAGUGCCCGGAGAGAAGCCUGAGCUGCCGGCAUUGCCGGGCACCCUGCUGCGGAGCAGACGUGAAGGCGCACCACGAGGUCUGCCCCAAGUUCCCCUUAACUUGUGACGGCUGCGGCAAGAAGAAGAUCCCCCGGGAGAAGUUUCAGGACCACGUCAAGACUUGUGGCAAGUGUCGAGUCCCUUGCAGAUUCCACGCCAUCGGCUGCCUCGAGACGGUAGAGGGUGAGAAACAGCAGGAGCACGAGGUGCAGUGGCUGCGGGAGCACCUGGCCAUGCUACUGAGCUCGGUGCUGGAGGCAAAGCCCCUCUUGGGAGACCAGAGCCACGCGGGGUCAGAGCUCCUGCAGAGGUGCGAGAGCCUGGAGAAGAAGACGGCCACUUUUGAGAACAUUGUCUGCGUCCUGAACCGGGAGGUGGAGAGGGUGGCCAUGACUGCCGAGGCCUGCAGCCGGCAGCACCGGCUGGACCAAGACAAGAUUGAAGCCCUGAGUAGCAAGGUGCAGCAGCUGGAGAGGAGCAUUGGCCUCAAGGACCUGGCGAUGGCUGACUUGGAGCAGAAGGUCUUGGAGAUGGAGGCAUCCACCUACGAUGGGGUCUUCAUCUGGAAGAUCUCAGACUUCGCCAGGAAGCGCCAGGAAGCUGUGGCUGGCCGCAUACCCGCCAUCUUCUCCCCAGCCUUCUACACCAGCAGGUACGGCUACAAGAUGUGUCUGCGUAUCUACCUGAACGGCGACGGCACCGGGCGAGGAACACACCUGUCCCUCUUCUUUGUGGUGAUGAAGGGCCCGAAUGACGCCCUGCUGCGGUGGCCCUUCAACCAGAAGGUGACCUUAAUGCUGCUCGACCAGAAUAACCGGGAGCACGUGAUUGACGCCUUCAGGCCCGACGUGACUUCAUCCUCUUUUCAGAGGCCAGUCAACGACAUGAACAUCGCAAGCGGCUGCCCCCUCUUCUGCCCCGUCUCCAAGAUGGAGGCAAAGAAUUCCUACGUGCGGGACGAUGCCAUCUUCAUCAAGGCCAUUGUGGACCUGACAGGGCUCUAACUGCCCCCUACUGGUGUCUGGGGGUUGGGGGCAGCCAGGCACAGCCGGCUCACGGAGGGGCCACCACGCUGGGCCAGGGUCUCACUGUACAAGUGGGCAGGGGCCGCGCUUGGGCGCUUGGGAGGGUGUCGGCCUGCAGCCAAGUUCACUGUCACGGGGGAAGGAGCCACCAGCCAGUCCUCAGAUUUCAGAGACUGCGGAGGGGCUUGGCAGACGGUCUUAGCCAAGGGCUGUGGUGGCAUUGGCCGAGGGUCUUCGGGUGCUUCCCAGCACAAGCUGCCCUUGCUGUCCUGUGCAGUGAAGGGAGAGGCCCUGGGUGGGGGACACUCAGAGUGGGAGCACAUCCCAGCAGUGCCCAUGUAGCAGGAGCACAGUGGAUGGCCUUGUGUCCCUCGGGCAUGACAGGCAGAAACGAGGGCUGCUCCAGGAGAAGGGCCUCCUGCUGGCCAGAGCAAGGAAGGCUGAGCAGCUUGGUUCUCCCCUCUGGCCCCUGGAGAGAAGGGAGCAUUCCUAGACCCCUGGGUGCUUGUCUGCACAGAGCUCUGGUCUGUGCCACCUUGGCCAGGCUGGCUGUGGGAGAGGGUCUGGUCCCACGCCGCCUCUGCUCAGACCACUGUGUGGGAGGUGCACAGCACAGCCUGCGGGUAAAGUGUGAGAGCUUGCCAUCCAGCUCACGAAGACAGAGUUAUUAAACCAUUCAAAUCUC